GAGUGUGUAUGUGCGGGCGAGAAGAUGGCGGCGGCGGGGGAAGCAGCGUGAGCAGCCGGAGGAUCGCGGAGUCCCAAUGAAACGGGCAGCCAUGGCCCUCCACAGCCCGCAGUAUUAUCCCAGGGCUAGUUUCCCCCACGAUGGCGGAAUGGCCACAGCAGUUUCAGGCUUCACAUUUGGGCACAGCCUCCGUCACACCAGCCUGACCAAGAGAAUAUGCCAGUUCCUCCUGGACUCCUCAGACUGGAAGAUUGUCCUUUCUCCUUGGCAAAUCAUCUGUACUAUCUGAUUGCAUCUUACAGUCUUCUUUAAAUAUUAUUGUUCCUUAACUGUUAAUGUGUCUGUGCCUUGAGGUCAGCCUCAGGUUCCAAUCCUGUUCCAUUUUGUUUGUGGAAUCUCAGGCAAGUAUGUUUGGCAGAGAAAGCGGAAAUGGAGGUAGUGGCAUGAGUCAGCAGAAAGUAUAUUUUUGGAGAUUUUAGCCCUGAUGAAUUCAAUCAAUUCUUUGUGACUCCUCGAUCUUCAGUUGAGCUUCCUCCAUACAGUGGAACAGUUCUGUGUGGCACACAGGCUGUGGAUAAACUACCUGAUGGACAAGAAUAUCAGAGAAUUGAGUUUGGUGUCGAUGAAGUCAUUGAACCCAGUGACACUUUGCCGAGAACCCCCAGCUACAGUAUUUCAAGCACACUGAACCCUCAGGCCCCUGAAUUUAUUCUCGGUUGUACAGCUUCCAAAAUAACCCCUGAUGGUAUCACUAAAGAAGCAAGCUAUGGCUCCAUCGACUGCCAGUACCCAGGCUCUGCCCUCGCUUUGGAUGGAAGUUCUAAUGUGGAGGCGGAAGUUUUGGAAAAUGAUGGUGUCUCAGGUGGUCUUGGACAAAGGGAGCGUAAAAAGAAGAAAAAGCGGCCACCUGGAUAUUACAGCUAUUUGAAAGAUGGUGGCGAUGAUAGUAUCUCCACAGAAGCCCUGGUCAAUGGCCAUGCCAAUUCAGCAGUCCCGAACAGUGUCAGUGCAGAGGAUGCAGAAUUUAUGGGUGACAUGCCCCCGUCAGUUACGCCCAGGACUUGUAACAGCCCCCAGAACUCCACAGACUCUGUCAGUGACAUUGUGCCUGACAGUCCUUUCCCCGGAGCACUCGGCAGUGACACCAGGACUGCAGGGCAGCCAGAGGGGGGCCCCGGGGCUGAUUUUGGUCAGUCCUGCUUCCCUGCAGAGGCUGGCAGAGACACCCUGUCAAGGACAGCUGGGGCUCAGCCCUGCGUUGGUACCGAUACUACUGAAAACCUUGGAGUUGCUAAUGGACAAAUACUUGAAUCCUCGGGUGAGGGCACAGCUACCAACGGGGUGGAGUUGCACACCACGGAAAGCAUAGACUUGGACCCAACCAAACCCGAGAGUGCAUCACCUCCUGCUGACGGCACGGGCUCUGCAUCAGGCACCCUUCCUGUCAGCCAGCCCAAGUCCUGGGCCAGCCUCUUUCAUGAUUCUAAGCCCUCUUCCUCCUCGCCGGUGGCCUAUGUGGAAACUAAGUAUUCCCCUCCCGCCAUAUCUCCCCUGGUUUCUGAAAAGCAGGUUGAAGUCAAAGAAGGGCUUGUUCCGGUUUCAGAGGAUCCUGUAGCCAUAAAGAUUGCAGAGUUGCUGGAGAAUGUAACCCUAAUCCAUAAACCAGUGUCGUUGCAACCCCGUGGGCUGAUCAAUAAAGGGAACUGGUGCUACAUUAAUGCUACACUGCAGGCAUUGGUUGCUUGCCCGCCGAUGUACCACCUGAUGAAGUUCAUUCCUCUGUAUUCCAAAGUGCAAAGGCCUUGUACGUCAACACCCAUGAUAGACAGCUUUGUUCGGCUAAUGAAUGAGUUCACUAAUAUGCCAGUACCUCCAAAACCCCGACAAGCUCUUGGAGAUAAAAUCGUGAGGGAUAUUCGCCCUGGAGCUGCCUUUGAGCCCACAUAUAUUUACAGACUCCUGACAGUUAACAAGUCAAGCCUGUCUGAAAAGGGUCGACAAGAAGAUGCUGAGGAAUACUUAGGCUUCAUUCUAAAUGGACUUCAUGAGGAAAUGUUGAACCUAAAGAAGCUUCUCUCACCAAGUAAUGAAAAACUUACGAUUUCCAACGGCCCCAAAAACCACUCGGUCAAUGAAGAAGAGCAGGAAGAACAAGGUGAAGGAAGCGAGGAUGAAUGGGAACAAGUGGGCCCCCGGAACAAGACUUCCGUCACCCGCCAGGCGGAUUUUGUUCAGACUCCAAUCACCGGCAUUUUUGGUGGACACAUCAGGUCUGUGGUUUACCAGCAGAGUUCAAAAGAAUCUGCCACUUUGCAGCCAUUUUUCACGUUGCAGUUGGAUAUCCAGUCAGACAAGAUACGCACAGUCCAGGAUGCACUGGAGAGCUUGGUGGCAAGAGAAUCUGUCCAAGGUUAUACCACAAAAACCAAACAAGAGGUUGAGAUAAGUCGAAGAGUGACUCUGGAAAAACUCCCUCCUGUCCUCGUGCUGCACCUGAAACGAUUCGUUUAUGAGAAGACUGGUGGGUGCCAGAAGCUUAUCAAAAAUAUUGAAUAUCCUGUGGACUUGGAAAUUAGUAAAGAACUGCUUUCUCCAGGGGUUAAAAAUAAGAAUUUUAAAUGCCACCGAACCUAUCGGCUCUUUGCAGUGGUCUACCAUCACGGCAACAGUGCGACGGGCGGCCAUUACACUACAGACGUCUUCCAGAUCGGUCUGAAUGGCUGGCUGCGCAUCGAUGACCAGACAGUCAAGGUGAUCAACCAGUACCAGGUGGUGAAACCAACUGCUGAACGCACAGCCUACCUCCUGUAUUACCGCCGAGUGGACCUGCUGUAAACCCUGUGUGCGCUGUGUGUGCGCCCAGUGCCCGCUUCGUAGGACACCACCUCACACUCACUUCCCGCCUCUCUUUAGUGGCUCUUUAGAGAGAAACUCUUUCUCCCUUUGCAAAAAUGGGCUAGAAUGAAAAGGAGAUGCCUUGGGGUUCGUGCACAACACAGCUUCUGUUGACUCUAACUUCCAAAUCAAAAUCAUUUGGUUGAAACAGACUGUUGCUUGAUUUUAGAAAAUACACAAAAACCCAUAUUUCUGAAAUAAUGCUGAUUCCUGAGAUAAGAAAGUGGAUUUGAUCCCCAGUCUCAUUGCUUAGUAGAAUAAAUCCUGCACCAGCAACAACACUUGUAAAUUUGUGAAAAUGAAUUUUAUCUUUCCUUAAAAAAGAAAUUUUUUAAUCCAUCACACUUUUCUUCCCUACCCUUUAGUUUUUGAUAAAUGAUAAAAAUGAGCCAGUUAUCAAAGAAGAACUAGUUCUUACUUCAAAAGAAAAAUAAACAUAAAAAAUAAGUUGCUGGUUCCUAACAGGAAAAAUUUUAAUAAUUGUACUGAGAGAAACUGCUUACGUACACAUUGCAGAUCAAAUAUUUGGAGUUAAAAUGUUAGUCUACAUAGAUGGGUGAUUGUAACUUUAUUGCCAUUAAAAGAUUUCAAAUUGCAUUCAUGCUUCUGUGUACACAUAAUGAAAAAUGGGCAAAUAAUGAAGAUCUCUCCUUCAGUCUGCUCUGUUUAAUUCUGCUGUCUGCUCUUCUCUAAUGCUGCGUCCCUAAUUGUACACAGUUUAGUGAUAUCUAGGAGUAUAAAGUUGUCGCCCAUCAAUAAAAAUCACAAAGUUGGUUUAAA